ACAAAGGAAGUGAACUUGGAGAUGGCCAGCAGCUCCAUGUCACACAGCAAUGACACUGACAUAAAUGGCUCUUGAGAGCAAGGACUGGCAGGACCUGGCUACAGAUAUGGGGACUCACGUUGAGGUGGCACUGCUCACCUGGAGCAGCACACUGGAGUCACCUGGGACCAGCCUCCUAGAAGUCCAGAUGCGCCCGCCUGCCAGAGAGCUCCGAGAUUUUUCAAAACUCCUAGAGACAGUGGUUUUCAGCAACGGCGGGCACAUUAGCAUCACCCGGGACCCUGAAAAAGCCGGUUGGCCCAGGCGGCCCUCGCCCAGACCAAUUCAUCAGAACCUCUUGGGGUGGGGUGGGGCGGGGCUGGGAUGGGGAGCGGCAGCCGGGGUAUCAAUAUUUUUGAAAACUGCCUGAAUAACUCCAACGCUCAAGCAAGUCAAGGACACCCACGGACUCAACACCGCGACCAGAUUGGAAAAGGUGUUGGUCGACAACUUCUGCAUUUGCGAAGAGUGCAGCGUCCCUCGCUGUCUCAUGUAUGAGAUUUACGUGGAGACCUGUGGGCAAAACACUGAGAACCAAGUCAACCCGGCCACCUUUGGGAAGCUUGUGAGAUUGGUUUUUCCGGACCUUGGCACCCGGAGGCUGGGCACUAGAGGAAGUGCCAGGUAUCAUUAUGAUGGAAUCUGUAUCAAGAAAAGCUCUUUCUUCUAUGCCCAGUAUUGCUACCUGAUAGGUGAAAAAAGGUAUCACAGUGGAGAUGCCAUUGCCUUUGAAAAAUCUACUAAUUAUAACAGCAUUAUCCAACAAGAAGCAACAUGUGAAGAUCAUUCACCGAUGAAGACAGACCCAGUUGGAUCCCCUUUGUCUGAAUUCAGGAGAUGUCCAUUUCUGGAGCAAGAACAGGCAAAGAAAUACUCCUGUAAUAUGAUGGCCUUCCUUGCUGACGAAUACUGCAACUAUUGUCGAGACAUUUUACGAAAUGUGAGGAACUGAGAACUUGAGAGGGUGGAGGACUUGCUUACUUCCUUCUGGAAGUCUCUGCAGCAAGACACAGUCAUGCUGAUGUCAUUGCCUGACGUGUGCCAGCUCUUUAAAUGCUACGACGUCCAGCUGUACAAGGGAAUUGAGGAUGUUCUCCUUCAUGACUUCUUGGAAGAUGUUUCUAUUCAGUACCUGAAAUCUGUGCAGUUAUUUAGUAAGAAAUUUAAGCUGUGGCUCCUUAAUGCUUUGGAAGGUGUUCCAGCCCUCUUGCAGAUCUCCAAACUCAAAGACUAUGCGAAUGGUAUUGAAAAGUAAGAGGCGUGUCAGCGUUUUGAAGUCAGAUCUACAGGCCAUCAUCAAUCAAGGCACUUUGGCUACUUCUAAGAAAGCCCUGGCAAGUGACCGGAGUGGCGCAGAUGAACUGGAGAACAACCCAGAGAUGAAAUGUUUAAGAAACUUAAUUUCUUUGCUGGGAACAUCAACAGAUCUCAGGGUAUUCCUCAGCUGUCUGUCUUCACAUCUCCAAGCAUUUGUGUUCCAGACAAGCAGAAGCAAAGAAGAGUUUACCAAAUUGGCCGCCAGCUUCCAGCUGAGAUGGAAUCUUCUUCUCACUGCUGUAAGCAAAGCCAUGACCCUCUGCCACAGAGAUAGUUUUGGCUCCUGGCAUCUGUUUCACUUGUUGCUUUUGGAAUAUAUGAUUCAUAUACUUCAGUCAUGCCUAGAGGAGGAAGAGGAGGAGGAGGACAUGGGGACUGUCAAGGAAAUGCUACCAGAUGACCCGACUCUCGGCCAGCCAGACCAGGCACUUUUCCAUUCUCUGAAUUCCUCACUGUCGCAGGCGUGUGCCAGCCCCAGCAUGGAGCCACUGGGGGUGAUGCCCACACACAUGGGCCAGGGCCGAUAUCCCGUGGGUGUGAGCAACAUGGUCCUCAGGAUCCUGGGCUUCCUGGUGGACACUGCCAUGGGCAAUAAGCUCAUCCAGGUGCUGUUGGAAGAUGAAACCACUGAAAGCGCAGUUAAACUCAGCCUUCCUAUGGGACAAGAAGCCCUCAUAACCCUAAAAGAUGGACAACAAUUUGUGAUUCAGAUAUCAGAUGUACCCCAAAGCUCUGAAGAUAUUUAUUUCAGAGAAAACAAUGCUAAUGUGUGAGAUUAUUUAUUUGAAUAGAGAAUAAGAAAACUGAUAGACUUGCAUUCUUAAAAAUAUUAAAUACUAAAGUUUUUCUAUUGACGAAAGAUGAUGUUAUGUAUAUAAUAGAUGUAGCAUUGUCUAUUUUAUGUUUAUAUGUAUUUCAAGGAGGUGGUUUCGAUAAAAUAUGUAAACUGAUUUGGAGAAUAA